AAGGCCCAGACGGCUCUCAGAUCCGGGGGCUGCGGAUAAAUCCCCGUAGGCCGCGGGCAGCGAGAUGUUGCGUUCCGGUGUGGGUGUGGGUGUGCCUCCGACGGCGUCUCGGUGCCAGUGUCGAGGUUCUUUCUGCUUAGCUACCCGGAGCCGACUACGGAGGAGGACACCUGAGUUUACGUCUCUUCCAUCUGCUGCUCACCUCAGCUGCCUGGGUCCCCGACGAGAGCCAGGUGACACUUAACUCCGCCAUCUGCGUUUUGAGCACUGUUCUCAUAAUGGAGUUUCCUGAUUUGGGGAAGCAUUGUUCAGAAAAGACUUGCAAGCAGCUAGAUUUUCUUCCAGUAAAAUGUGAUGCAUGUAAACAAGAUUUCUGUAAAGAUCAUUUUCCAUACGCUGCACAUAAGUGUCCGUUUGCAUUCCAGAAGGAUGUUCACGUCCCAGUAUGCCCACUCUGUAAUACCCCCAUCCCAGUAAAAAAGGGCCAGAUACCAGACGUGGUGGUUGGUGAUCACAUUGACAGAGACUGUGACUCUCACCCUGGGAAGAAGAAAGAGAAGAUUUUUACAUACCGUUGCUCAAAAGAGGGCUGCAAGAAGAAAGAGAUGCUGCAGAUGGUAUGUGCCCAAUGUCACGGCAACUUCUGUAUCCAGCACAGACACCCUUUGGACCACAGCUGCAGACACGGGAGUCGCCCCACCAUCAAAGCUGGGUGCUCACCCAUGACAGUCUCUGAAUCCAGGCCGUUGGGAGAUUUCCUCACCCUGGCUCCUGGCGGGCUGGCCCAGCGACUCGGGUACUGGUUCACCCGGCUCAUGUGAACGCAAUUUCGUCUGUGUGGGGUGCUGCAGCUCUUGGUUGGUGAACACGGAAAGGUUGCUGUGUGUAACUGCACAGUGUGACGCGAUGCUCCAGUGGUGCGACUUCGUCAGGAUGGAUGAAGGACACAGGACUGGGACCCCAAGUUACAGAAGCAGCUCGCUCCAGCACAACCUUUCGGCAGCAGCAGCAUCAUACAGCUGGUUUCUGAAACACCUUUUCUGCCCUCCAAGAUCCUCUGACAUGAUCAACAUUCCUGCAUCAUCAAGACAAACCUGAAAAGAGCUGUUCUUUGUUCUUUUUGGUGGAAAGUGAUGAGGUCCUUCCCGUUUGCACUGCCGUGUGGGUUAUUUCCACUCUAGGUAACUUCCGCCUUCAGGUACUCCCCAUACUUCUAAUGGCCCAGCAGCACCUCCGGGCCAUCUUCACGGGAAUCCCCAGCUUCAAUGCUGGCUGGCUUUGCUUUUUUUUUUUUAAAAGGGAUGAAGUCUUGCUCUAUUGCCCAGGCUGGAGUGCAGUGGCACAAUCUCAGCUCACUGCCACCUCUGCCUUCCAGGUUCUAGCAAUUCUCCUGCCUCAGCCUCCCGAGUAGCUGGGAUUACAGGCACCAAACUGCCAUGCCCGGCUAAUCUUUUAUAUUUUAGUGAAGAUGGUUAGCCUGAAACCUUGAAACUUCCCCACUGAAAUACACAAACUAGGCCGGGCGUAGUGGCUCACACCUGUAAUCUCAGCACUUUGGGAGGGCAAGGUGGGUGGAUCACCUAAGGUCAGGAGUUCAAAACCAGCAAACACCAGACAGCUCACUUGCGCUCUUCACCAUGUCACCUCUGUAACGAUGUGACUAUCUGGCCAAGAAGGGGGAAGGACAUCCACCUGCCUGGCCGAGGGUUCUUGUCCAGCGGCGGCCACAGGUGCUACUCGCAUUGUUUGAGGGCACAGCUGCGUGCCCGUUCCUGACCUCCAAGGGGCUGGGACACUGUGUGAGAGAAGGUGUGUCUUCCUGGACCACUUGUCCCUGCCACGGUCAACUUCUUAAAACAGGCACAGUUCAGCCAGGCGCAGUGGCUCACGCUUGUAAUCUCAGCACUUUGGGAGGCGGAGGCAGGCGGAUCACCUGAGGUCAGGAGUUUGAGACCAGCCUGGUCAACAUGGUGAAACCCCAUGUCUACUAAAACAAAAAUUAGCCAGGUGUGGUGGUGGUACACGCUUGUAAUCCUAGCUACUCAGGAGGCUGAGGCAGGAGAAUCACUUGAACCUGGGAGGCGGAGGUUGCAGUGAGCCCAGAUUGUGCCACUGCACUCCAGCCUGGGCAACAGAGCAAGACUGAAUCUCAAAAAAAAAAAAAAAAAAGGCACAGUUGUCAGCAGCCAGCAAGCCCGAGAGCUGCUUUGCACCUGGAUCUAUUUCAGCACCAACAAGAAAGUUGCAAAAUGCCACCUGUUGAAGAUGGCUCUGUCCAGUGAUGAAGCAGUGGAAACUUCCAGAAGUGACUUAAAACUACAAUGGCAGGAACUAGGGCUUCCACAAGUGCCAGAGAUUACAGGAGACUGGGUUUUAUAGGUUUGAAGAGCAGAAAGCCAAAACGGGAGGGAAGGGGGGUAGUGAGGUGCACAGUCCUUUGUGGCUCAGAUGACAGAUGCGGCCUUCGUGGCCUGACACUUUCCACCACCGUCUGAUUUUGUGAAGUGAUGAACACGGGUAACGUAAAUACUGGUGUUAGAUUUAUACUGACAGCCGCUCUGCUCAUCAAGAGUGCAGUGAUUUCCUGGGAACUUAGGGGGUGUCAGGGAAUAAGGUGAAACAAAAUUCCCCCAAGUUCUGUCCUGUUCUGAACUGCCCUGGCCAUCCAGCUGUGCCCACCAGAUGUCCCGCUGAGACAGUUCACAAAAACACAAGCCACUGCCUUUUUUUUUUCUGCUUUCACCAUCUAAAAAUGUAACGGGAAGGGUUUGUAUUCUGUUGGCGUUCUGCAAAAAGGUGGUCAGACCUGCAGUCAGGGGAACGAUGUUUCUGUCGAUGACGGACCGUGUAUAUGUUGGUGAUCGCAGAACAUACUGUAUUUUCACUAUAUCUUUUUUUUUUAAUCUGACAAACUUUUUUGCUUUUAUUUUAAUUGACAUAAUUGUACAUAUUGAUGGGGUACAUUGUGGUAUUUGGAGGAGUUUGAGACCAGCCUGGCCAACAUGAUGAAACCCUGUCCCUACUAAAAAUACAAAAAUUAGCCGGGCGUGGUGGUGCAUGCCUGUAAUCCCAGCUACUUGGGAGGCUGAGGCAAGAGGAUCGCUUGAACCCGGGAGGCAGAGGUUGCAGUGAGCAGAGAUCGUGCCAUUGCACUCCAGCCUGGGUGAUAGAGCAAGACUCCAUCUCAAAAAAAAAAAAAAAAACUUAAGAACAAGCUAGUCACCCUGCAGUCCCACAGAACACUGGGAUGGAAUCCUCCCAGCAAGCUGGACCGCACCACGCCUAGGUUUGGAAGCACAAACACGCAGCGCCGUGCCGCAGUGGCCUACAGCAUUCAGCGCAGUAGCACUCUGCACGCAUUUGUAGCCUGGGAGCCACAGGCUAUGCCCUACAGCCUGGGUGUGGAGGAGGCCGCACCAUCGAGCUCUGUGUAAGUCCCUGUAGGAUGCUUGCACGACAAUGCAAUCACCUGGCCGUGCACAUCCCUGACGGUGGGUGACAUGUGACCGUUGCUAUGCUUAUUUCAUGGUGUCUGUCCUAGGCCGGCGGUUCCCAAGCCCUAGCCUGUGUCAAAACACAGGGCUCCUUACGGGAGGGUGCUGGACCCCACCCCGAGGCCCUGGUUCUGUGGUCUGAGGUGGACUCAGGUUUACACCUGGAGCUGCCCGGGUGACACGUCUGGUCUGGGACUGCACUUGGACAAGCCACUUCCCUGCGUCUGCAGCACCUCUGGCCUCGUGUGCUGUGGAGCAAGGAAAACGCAGCCAGCACAGUGUUCGGUGUGGUUAAGUUUAAAAACCACUAACUUGGUUCAGUCAGUGGAAAACAGGUACGUUAGGAACCUGGGUGUGUGAACUGUGAAUCUGCAGAUCAGGUGUUCUAAUGAAAAAAUGUUUUUAAUUUUUAAAGUCUUGAGAAACAAAGUUCUGAUAAUUUAAUGUCCAAACUGAGAUGUAUCCAGCCGGGCCCAGUGGCUUAUGCCCGUAAUCGCAGUACCUUGGGAGGCUGAUGUGGGCGGAUUGCUUGAGCCCAGAUGUUUGAGAUAGGACUGGGCAAUGUAGUAAGACGUUGUCUCUCAAAAAAAAUAAAUAGCCAGACAGAUGGUGCAUGCAUGUGGUCCCAGUUACUCAGGAGACGUCAAGGCUGCAGUGAGCUGUGAUCACACCACUGCACUCCAGCCUGGGUCACAGAGAGCAAGACUGUCUCA